AGUGUCCUCAGCUGCCUCCGCGCGCCAAAGUCAAACCCCGACACCCGCCGGCGGGCCGGUGAGCUCACUAGCUGACCCGGCAGGUCAGGAUCUGGCUUAGCGGCGCCGCGAGCUCCAGUGCGCGCACCCGUGGCCGCCUCCCAGCCCUCUUUGCCGGACGAGCUCUGGGCCGCCACAAGACUAAGGAAUGGCCACCCCGCCCAAGAGAAGCUGCCCGUCUUUCUCAGCCAGCUCUGAGGGGACCCGCAUCAAGAAAAUCUCCAUCGAAGGGAACAUCGCUGCAGGGAAGUCAACAUUUGUGAAUAUCCUUAAACAAUUGUGUGAAGAUUGGGAAGUGGUUCCUGAACCUGUUGCCAGAUGGUGCAAUGUUCAAAGUACUCAAGAUGAAUUUGAGGAACUUACAAUGUCUCAGAAAAAUGGUGGGAAUGUUCUUCAGAUGAUGUAUGAGAAACCUGAACGAUGGUCUUUUACCUUCCAAACAUAUGCCUGUCUCAGUCGAAUAAGAGCUCAGCUUGCCUCUCUGAAUGGCAAGCUCAAAGAUGCAGAGAAACCUGUAUUAUUUUUUGAACGAUCUGUGUAUAGUGACAGGUAUAUUUUUGCAUCUAAUUUGUAUGAAUCUGAAUGCAUGAAUGAGACAGAGUGGACAAUUUAUCAAGACUGGCAUGACUGGAUGAAUAACCAAUUUGGCCAAAGCCUUGAAUUGGAUGGAAUCAUUUAUCUUCAAGCCACUCCAGAGACAUGCUUACAUAGAAUAUAUUUACGGGGAAGAAAUGAAGAGCAAGGCAUUCCUCUUGAAUAUUUAGAGAAGCUUCAUUAUAAACAUGAAAGCUGGCUCCUGCAUAGGACACUGAAAACCAACUUCGAUUAUCUUCAAGAGGUGCCUAUCUUAACACUGGAUGUUAAUGAAGACUUUAAAGACAAAUAUGAAAGUCUGGUUGAAAAGGUCAAAGAGUUUUUGAGUACUUUGUGAUCUUGCUGAAGACUACAGGCAGCCAAAUGGUUCCAGAUACUUCAGCUUUGUGUAUCUUCGUAACUUCAUAUUAAUAUAAGUUUCUUUAGAAAACCCAAGUUUUUAAUCGUUUUUGUUUUAAGGAAAAAAGAUUUUUAAAAUGAAUCUUAUGCAAAACUUUUUGACCAGUUUCUUUUCUUUUGUUUUUUUUUUAAAAAAGACAUUUAAAGACAAAGACAUUAUUUCUCAUAGCAGGAAAUGUAGAGGUAGAUGGUUCCAGUAUCAGCAUAGUGACUAAACUACAUUAUAAAAGAUCCAGCUUCCUUCUGUCAUUCCCCUCUUUUGUCUUCCUCAGCAGGUUGGCUUUUUUCCCUGGUGCCUCUCACUUCGUUGGUGACCAGUUUCUUAAACUGAAAGCUUUAAUGUUACAUAGUAAAUGGUAGUGUGUCCUGUGUAAAUUAGUGUACCUAUUAAAAGUUGCAAAGUGGAAUUAAAGGAAUCCCUAGAAUAAGGAUUCUGAAGUUUUAUUUUAAAUUAUUAUCUUCUUAACAGUUUAGUCCCACCUCUUACUUCCUGCCUCAGUCUGCUUUCUCUACUGUCUGGAUUAAUUAGGCAGCCUGCUAUAAAGUUAAAGUCACACAUUUCUAUUUUGCAAACACUGUGAUUACUCUUUGCUUUGUAGUUUGCUUUGCUUUGUAGGGUUCUGCUUUUAAGUUUUUCUCUUUUUCAGACAAAUUACUGAUAAAAAUGAUAUUGCUCUAUAUGUAAUAUAUCCUGAAAGCAUUAUUUUUUGUUGAAUAGGAAAUAAAAUUAAUGAAGACAGAGGCUAGAAAGCAUCCAUUAAUUAAUGAGACACACUUAACUACUUAUCUCUAAACCAUCUAUGUGAAUAUUUGUAAAAAUAAUGAAUGGACUCAUCUUAGUUCUGUAUAUAAAUAUAUUUUCUUUCUAGUUUGUUUAGUUAAGGUGUGCAGUGUUUUUCCUGUGUAUUAAACCUUUCCAUUUUACGUUUUAGAAAAUUUUAUGUAUUUUAAAAUAAGGGGAAGAGUCAUUUUCACUUUUAAACUACUAUUUUUCUUUCCAAGUCAUUUUUGUUUUUGGUUUCUUAUUCAAAGAUGAUAAUUUAGUGGAUUAACCAGUCCAGACGCACUGAUCUUUGCAAAGGAGACUUAAUUUCAAAUCUGUAAUUACCAUACAUAAACUGUCUCAUUAUACGUAUGCAUUUUUUUAGUUUGUUUUUGUUUGGUAUAAAUUAAUUUGUUAAUUAAAUAUUUCUUAAGUAUAAACCUUAUGAACUACAGUGGAGCUACACUCAUUGAAAUGUAAUUUCAGUUCUAAAAAGAUGUAAUAAUCAUUUUAGAAUUAAAAUUUAUUCUACUUUUAAAUAAAUUAUGAAUAUUAAAGGUGAAAAUUGUAUAAAUUACUUUGAUUCCAUUUUAAGUGGAGACAUAUUUCAGUGAUUUUUAGUAACCUUUAAAAAUGUAUAAUGACUUUUAAAAUUUGUAGAAUUGAAAAGACGCUAAUAAAAAUUUAUUAUUUAUUUGUCAUGACUCAAAA